AGCCGGCGCUGGGCUGAGCUUGUGGCAGAAGGGAGGUAAGCCGUGCGGGGCGGCGGGCUGCCACCGCUGCACCCCUGCUCGGGAGCCGCCGGGUCGCGCCGCCUGCGGCCCGGUCGGCUUGCAUGGAGGGCGGCUGAGGCCCUGCGGGGCUGGGGCUGAGCUGGGAGACGGGGCAGUGGAGCAUGUGGCGGCAGGGCCGCGUCGCGGCGAGGGGCAGCCGGGAGGGGGCUUUUUGCCCUCGUCCGGUCCUGCUGGGGCUCUCAGCUUCUGGAGGACUAGGCCUUCUGAGGUUACGGAGCUCCGAGAUACCUGGGCAGGGCUGGCUGUGGUGACUGCGGUGGGACUUAGUGGGAUCUCGACUCGGAAGCCGGUCGGCGCGAUCCUUGCAUACUUAGCUGCAGCAGGUUGCAGUCGUCCCACUCUCCUUCGACCGGUUCCCUAGUUGGGGGCAGAGCAGGAGAUUCUGGCCGCGUCCUGCCUGGCCUGGGGUGACUGUCUCCUUCUCAUUCCCGGUGACUCACUCAGAUCAUGUCCACUUAUAAUGCAAAGGCUUAUGGGUGAGCAGGGCCUGUUUUCAGUCUCCUAGUUCUCUGGCUCCGUCCGCACUUGCGGCAAUUACUUGAAGAAAGAGUAUGUUAGAUGUAUGUUUUGAAAUUUUCGCAGCAGCUAACGCGUGGAGACGUGCAGUUAUGUUGCAUUUACCCUUCAUGAGUUUUAGUUUCAGCUGUGGCGUCCUGAUAUCUCAGUGUGGUUCCUGAAUUUGGAGCUUUUGAAAUGAAUGAAAUCCUGCCAAUUUCAUGCAGUCAUUCAUUCAUACAUUCCAAACUUUUUUGAUGGAUGCCUUAAUGGUCAGCCUCAUACCAGGUUCUAGUAUCCCUGAAACCAUCGUGGCUCUGAGGGUGUAAUCCUGAUAACUGUAUCAGUAAUGACUCCAGGUUUCAGUGGCCUAUCUGUAAGAAGAGGAAUGGGAUUAGUAUAAUUUUGAGAUUUUCCAGGAGAGGAGGGUAGAUGGCAUGUUUCCUGAACUGUGUUAACAGGAAGUAACUAUUUUAAAAACACAGGAUGCAUUUUAUGAUUAUGUUUUACUGUGUCAACGAACAUUGUAUCUGUCCACAUUCACUUUUUGACUACCAAGCAAGUGCAUGUUUACAAUUUUGAUUCACAUCCAAUUCCUGCGUAGAAAGCACUGUGACUCAUCUGAAUUUUGAAAUGAAGUAAUCAUGAGCUUUUUAAUGUUACAUACAAAGGUAUGAUAUUGAAACAAUUGCAUAAAAAUGCAAUUUUCAAAGCAUUUUCACUUGCUUUUAUAGAUUAGUGGAAGCUAAAACCUCUGCCUUGAUUAUUUGCUUACUUAAUCAAUGUUAGGUAGUUACCAUCUCUUGGCUAAUGUUUAUCAAUAUUAUAUCUAUUUUAACAUUUGUUUCAUUAACCCCAAAUUUACUGGAUUUUAACUGAUUGUUGUCUCCAGUUGACGCCUGAUAACCAAAAGGUUAUCAGGAGGAGCUGGAGGAGGCGGAACACAGCCUCGCGCCCUGUAAUAAAUAGUUUGAAAUCAAAAUUUUCAUGGACGUAUAACCAGAGUUUUUCAUUUGUUGAUUGAUUGAUGGUGCUUACCGGUAAAUCGUUUGGCCUUUUUCCCCGUUUAAAAUGAUUUAUGAAACAGUCUGAGACAUAAUAUUCUUAGCUUCAUGAUACUUUUGGGAUAUUGUCCACAAGUGAUUAGUUGAAUUAAAUUGUUAAUAUCACUAUUAGGAGUUUGGAAAAUUUAAGAAAAUAUAACUUCUUAAAAUUUUGCAUUUGCUAUUUUUUUGUUUGUUUGGAGACAGGGUCACUCUGUCGCCCAGGCUGGAGUGCAGUGCUGCGAUCUCGGCUCACUGCAACCUCCGCCUCCCAGGUUCAAGUGAUUCUUCUGCCUCAGCCUCCUAAGUAGCUGGGAUUACAGGCGCAUGCCACCACACCCAGCUAAUUUUUGUAUUUUUAGUAGAGACGGAGUUUCACCAUGUUGGCCAGGCUGGUCUCGAAAUCCUGACCUCAAGUGAUCCCUCCGCGUUGGUGUUACAUCUUUCAGUUCUAGAAAUGGACCUGAUCAAGAUUGCAAGGUUAAUGGGGAAAAUUCAAGAGCUGAGGACAUUAACCUUCUAGCGGGAAAAAACCACAAUGAGAAAUAAUAACUAUAUUUGGAGGAAGUGUAAGGAAAUAAUAGUUUAAGGAUUAUUAGUCUAUAACAAAUCUUGAUCUUAAUCAGUAUUUCUUGAUGUAUAACAAAGAACUUGGUUUAAGCACAAAAAGAAAAUUAGGGUGAUAAUUUAAAUUUUGAUCAAGUGGGUAGUAAGUAUUUCUUUAGGAGAUGAGAAAUCUAUAGAUCUAGAGAUGCAUGGUAUAAUAAAGUAUGGUAUACUUAUAUGAGUAUAAGUCUGUGAUUCACAAUUAGUAAUAGAUUGAUGGAGGUUUUGUUACUAUUUCCACAUGAUAAGAAACAAGAUUUGCUAAGCUGAUAGGACAAGGGAUAUUUGUGAAUUUCCUCCAUGUAAAUGAUUUGAAACAACAAAGUUUUAAGUGAUGUGGAAGAGCCCAUCUAUUUUCAAACAAUGGAUUGAAAUGUAGUUUUUGUAACCCUCUAAGUACUUCUGGCCUCAUAGUUUUUUUUUUUUUUCCCCCUACUCAGGUCAUAUUGAAAGUAAUAAAAUUGUGUUUAUGAUUUUAAAAGUUUAUAUUGGCUUUCAUUUAAUUAGUCUGAGUUACUUUAGUUUUAUAUAUUUUGAAGAUGUUCCAAAACCCUUGACUUUAAAUACUGUAUAGCUUUCCAUUGUUCAUGAAAGAAAACAUUUCUUUAGGCCAAAGGAAAUUGAGAAUCCAACUUGCAUAGAUAGUCAGUUUAUUACUAUUAUUUAAAGAUUUAUCUUUUUACUUGCCCGGGGACCAAUGAAGCAUCCACUGAAGCUCCUAAACUGGAGAAGGUAUCUUCUAAUCUCCUUUUGGUCAGAUGAGUUCUUGCUAAUUUGGCUGAUACAUAUGUUGAACAAAUGUAAUACAGUAAUUGUGGGUGUUGUAACUGUAGUUUUAUGAAGUUUUUUUGGUUGCCAGGGUGUAUCUUUCCCUUCUCUCUUGACAAACCUUUCUAUUUGGCCUACCUGCUUUCAUAAUUUAUUCUUAAGUUCUACUCUAUUUCCCAAUCAUUGCACAUGUUGGUUUAUGUAACCAAACCUGAUUUUAGUAUAUGCUAUUAGGACAUACACGUGGAGAAGAAUGGAGGAAACUUUUUAUUAAAUGUUUUUAAUUGUUGAAACACUUAAGUAAAUGUGAUUUUUAAAGACUCAUAGUUAUUAAAGGUAUUGUAUUCAUUAUUUUUUAUUUAUUCCUUCAUUCAGCAAAGACAGCAACUACUUUGGUGCUAGGUCCUUAACUUAUCUUUAAGGAACUUACAGUAUUGCAUGGACUUCAUAAACAACACCAAAAUACAAUGGGAUAAACAUUAUAAUUAGUCGUUCACAUAGUAUAGUGGGGGAUAGAGAAAACUGUGUGCAAGGUUUGAGGAGAUUCAGAGAAGGCUUUAUGGAGGAAUUUUCAUCUGAAUUGAAGUUUGAAAGUGAGUAGGAAUUAGUUGGUGAGGUUAGAGGAUAAGGCAUUCUGGGCACAAGAAAGCAGUGAGGACAAAUAGAUAGGUUAGAAACGGGACAUAGACCCUUAAUGUGUUAAGAUAGAGAAUAGAUCAACUUUAAAAAGUAAACAAGGGUAAAUAAUGAAAGUUCUCUUCCACACCGUGUUAGCCAUUUUGAGCUUUAAUCUGGAGGCUAUGUUGAUCCAUGAGUAAUAGAUUUUAAGUGGAAGAAAGUUAACAUCAGUUUCAUGAGGCAAUGUGAGGAAUGAAUUGUAGUGGGGUAAGGCAGACAUUUGCAUUACAUGUGACAGAACUCCGAAAAUGCAGUGCUGCUGGAGAGAAGAGGAUGAAUUCCAGAUAUAUUAAGGUGAUUGAGUUAGUGGCCAGAUGGAUGUAGGGGAUGAAGGAGUGAUGGAGUCAAGGAUACCUCCUAGGUUUAUGACUUGCCGAGAUAGGAAUCACAUGAGCAAUAUCAGAUGUAUGGGGAGAAUAAGAUCAGUAGUCUUGGACAUGGGUUUAGGUCACACAAUUGGUGCUGUUCAGUGGGUAUUUGGCUGCUUUGGCCUGGAGUUAAAGAGAGGAUUCUAGGCUGGAGAUAGAGAUUAGGAUGCUAUCAAUUUAUAGGUAGUUAAAACAAUGUGAGAAUGGAUGAUGCCUAAGAGAGUUUGUAGAAUAAGAAAGAAUAAAGCAGAAGGGAAACGCUGGGAAACACUACCCUGUAGGAAAGAUGACCCAGUGAAAAAGACAGAAGGAACAGCCUAAUGACAGUGGAUGUCUAGAAGAUAAGGAGGGAGAGAAUCCAACAAGAAGAGACUGGUCAGAUGCCAUAGGGAAUAGGAGAAAGAGCUAACUACAGUUUUUGGAAGGUUUCCCAGAUAGGCCUGGAUCAUUAAUUUGUAAUAAUACUAGUUCAUAUGAUUCUGUGACUUUUGGCAGCAAAAUUCAGUAGAACCAGAGAUGAUAAAUAGUUGGAUUGAUACAGUAUUUGGAUUUUGUUACGUGCGUAUGGUAAGAUUGCAAAGGAGUUGAAACUAUUGGUGAAAGAAUGGUCAGAGUGAUGGAAUGUGAAGUUUAGACUGGAUAGGGAUGACGAUAGAGCCAGGAGGAGCUGAAAGAUUGAGAUAACAUAAUUGGUUCAAAGGAUUAAAAGUCUGGAUGAAGUAAAUAUACAAGUGUUUGUAGCUAAAAGGGAGAUAAUGAAAAGGAUAGAAAUCCUCUGGUCAGAGUAGAAUAUUGGAAUUUAAGAUUUUUAGGGUGCAGAUGGCGUGUAGGGUUUGGCUGUGGAUAUAGAUGGUAGAAACGGAGGUGUUCAGGAACAAUGAGACUGGUGGUGCAUUCGAUGAAUUGCUCACCCAGAUGACUGUAGAUGACUGUGGUACCCAGGGAGGAAGGGUAGAAUGUGAUCCUAAUUUCCGAGGUUUAGAUUGCCUAUGGUGGUGAUCACUAUAGAUGAGAGAUGAAGAUACUUAGAUGUUAUGCCCUCAAAAGUACAGCGGGUGGGGGUGGGAUGGGGUAAGUGGUCUGGAAACAUUCUUCUGGGCCUUGGGACUUGGAAGGAUGAUUAGCCUUUACUGGUGGGGGCCACCAAAGAAGGGGAGUUUAAUUUCUAUUAGGCCUAGGAGGUAUGGGGAGCAUCUAGUGAAGAGGCUGAGGAUAUAAGAAAGCUUAUUGACUAUGGUGUCAGUGUAAAAGCUUGGGAAGGAGUGAGAGAGCGAGUAAAGAUUAUUUAGAGGAGAAGACAGGUUAGAAAGAGCUUAGAUUUGGGUAUAAGGGUGACAGCGCUUCUCUGAAGCAUAUGGCUAGCUUUUAGUAGUUGGGACUUUAAAUUUUGAUGAAGCUUUCUGUUGUUAACGUUUACCCAUCAAGUCAUUAUAGUUUCUGUCAGAGUAGGACAGUUGGCAUAGUACUGUUUCUAAAUUUAAAAAUAACAUAUAUGUCUCCAGUGAAUAUUUGUGUUAUCUGUCGGAGAAAGGAUGGACAGUGUGGCCUAUUUGCUUUGAUGUACCUUUUCCUGGUCUUUGAAUUCCCAAAAUACUUUUGCAAAUACAUUUCAUCAUGUGUGCCAAUUCUUAUCUAUUGGUAGGAUUAGGAAGUUAUGUUGAGUAUUUUUAGGUCAAUUCUGGGCCCAGAGGUAUAGGAAAUGCCUUAAUGUGAAUGGCAAUUGCCAUGAAUGUGGGAGAUUGGCAUACCUGCAUUUACCUAAGAUUGCCAUCUGUUAUUUUCUGACCUAGAGUCUGUUUCUAAGGACAGCGCCUCACUUAUGCACUAGGUCUUAUUCCUUUUACCUUCCGAAGGAUUUGGCUCCAGCAUCUCUCUCUCUGAACAUUGCAUUUCCCCUAAUUACUGGAUUAUUCCGUUCAUUAUGCAAGUAUGCUGGUAUUUUUCCAUGUUAAAAUAAUAGCUUUUGACCCCAUUCCUGCUUAAGCCACUGUACAAUUUAUUUGUUACCCCUUAUGGUAUAACUAUAAUCCUGUCCAAUUUCUUUCCUUCUAUUCUUUCUUAAACCCACUUUAAUCAGGCUUUCUCCCUCACCUCUAUCAAAAAAUUACUCUUACUAAAAGUAACUUUUCUGAGAAGUUACUUUUCUAAAAGUGACUUUAUUUUUCAUCUAGAGACAGAGUCUUGCUCUGUCGCCCUCUCUGAAGUGCAGUGGUGUGAUCAUAGCUCGCCACAGCCUUGAACUCCUGGGCUCAAGUGGUACUUCUGCCUUGCCUCCUGAGUAGCUAGGACUGCAGAUAUGUGCCACCAUACCUGGCUAAUUUUUCUAUUUCUUGUAGCGGUGGGGGUCUUACCAUGUUGCUCAGGCUGUUUUGAACUUCUGGCCUCAAGCAAUCCUCCUGCCUGGGCCCAGAGUGCUGGGAUUAUAGGCGGAGGCACCAUGCCUGGCCCUUUCAUUUUCCUAAAUCUAAAGGUCUGUUCCAAAUUUUUACCUCUCAGUUGACCUGUCAGCAUUUUUUUUUUUUUUGAGACAGCUAGUCACUCUCUGCUUCUUUAUUUUUAUUUUUGAGACAGAGUCUCACUCUGUCGACCAGGCUGGAGUGCAGUGGCGUGACCUCGGCUCACUGCAACCUUCAUCUCUUGGGUUCAAGUGAUACUUCUGCCUUAGUCUCCUGAGUAGCUGGGAUUACCGGCAUGUGCCACCACACCCAGCUAAUUUUUGUAUUUUUAGUAGAGAUGGGGUUUCACCACGUUGGCCAGACUGGUCUUGAACUCCUGACCUCAAGUGAUCCACCUGCCUUGGCCUCCCAAAGUGCUGGGAUUACAGGUGUGAGCCAUAGUGCUGGCCCAAUCUCUGCUUCUUAAAGCACUUUCUUCCCUUAUUAGCAAAAAUACCACAAUUCCUGGUUUUCCUCCUACGUCAUUGUCCCUUUUUAGACUCCUUUACUGGUUCUUCCUUAUCUCCCUGAUAAGAGUGCUGUUAACAUUGGAGUGCUUCAGGGGUCAGUCAUUAGACCUUAUACUUCUGGAUCAUAUCAUUCAGCCUUUAAAUAUUAGCAUUAUUAUUAUUUAUUAAUUAAUUAAUUUUAUUUUAUUAUUAUUUUUUGAGAUGGAGUCUCGCUCUGUCCCCCAGGCUAGAGUGCAGUGGCGUCAUCUCGGCUCACUGCAAGCCGCACCUCCCGGGUUCACGCCAUUCUCCUGCCUCAGCCUCCUGAGUAGCUGGGACUACAGGUGCCCGCCACCAUGCCCAGAUAAUUUUUUGUAUUUUUAGUAGAGACGGGUUUCACCAUGUUAGCCAGGAUGGUCUCGAUUUCCUAACCUCGUGAUCUGCCCACUUCGGCCUCCCAAAGUGCUGGGAUUAUAGGCAUGAGCCACCAAGCCCGGCCAAUUUAUUUUUUGAGAUGGAGUCUCCCUCUGUCACCCAGGCUGGAGUGCACUGGCACGAUCUCGGCUCACUGCAACCUCCGCCUCCCGGGUUCAAGCGAUUCUCCUGCUUCAGCCUCUUGAGUAGCCGGGACUACAGGUGCGCACUACCACACCAGGCUAAUUUUUUUAUUUUUAGUAGAGACGUUGGCCAGGCUGAUCUCGAAAAAUGAUCCACCCGCCUUGGCCUCCCAAAGUGCUGGGAUUACAGGUGUGAGCCACGGCACCUGGCCUAAGUAUUAGCUUUAAAUACUAGUAAUACCCUACUAGCUUCCAAAUUUAUAUUUUCAGCCUCGCCUUCCCUUGAACUCCUGACUCCGUAUAUCCAGUGACUACUCAGCAUUUUCUGUUUGGAUGACUAAUAUAUAUUUCAAACUAAACUCUGAAAUUUCCUUUUUUACCUAUAAUCUUUCCUAUUUCAGUUAACAGAAACUCCAUCCUUUUUAUGAGAUAGGCUAAAAACCUGAGUAUCAUCCUUGACUCUUCUUUAUCUCACAAUCUAUAUAUAUAUACUGUUACUUUGGAAAGUGUGUUGGCUAUACCUUCACAAUGUAUUUAGAAUCCAAGUACUUGUCACUACCCACUGCUAUCACCCUAGUCUAAGCCCCCGUUGUUUAUGUCCGGAUCUUGCAGUAGCCUCUAUAUUAGUUAUCAAUUGUUACCUACUCCCAACAUUUUGUGGCUUAAACCAACAGUUAUGUAUUAGUUUGUGAUUCUGUGGUUGGCAGCUUAGGUUGGACUUGGGGUAGAUGUGGGGCAGCUCUUUUGCUGGUCUUGCCCGUGCUCACUCAUGUAGUGAUCGGCACUGGUAGGUUUGGAGGCCUCAGCUGAGAUGGCUUAUCUCUGCUCUACGUGGUCAGUAAACUAUCUCAUGUUUAUGUUUCUUUACGUAGUGGUGUAAUGGAAGCAAGAUAACAAGAGGAAACUAUGUGGCCUUUUGAGGCCGGGACUUAGAACUUCUACAGCUUCACUUUCCCUGCUGUUGGUGAGAGCAGGUCACCAGGUCAAGCCAGAUGAAGGGGAGAGAAAAUUAGCCUACUUUUUUUUCUGAGGGGGUGCAGCAAAGUCACUUUGUAAAGCAGUUUGUAUACAGAGAUUGGGAGCAAUUGGAGGCCAUUUUUUGCAAACUGUCCUGGCCUUCUAAUGGAUUGCUUCUAUCUUUCCCCUUACAGUAUUGUCAGAACAGCAGCCAGAGUGAUUUUAUAAAAACGUGAGUUAGAUCUCUUCUCUGCCCCAAACUCUCCAGUGGCUUCCCGUUGCCACCCAAAGUAAAAGGCAGUCUUGGGAUUGUCCUGUGAGGCUUGCCAUGAUCUGACCCAUUUGUUGCCUCUCCAACUCCAUUUACAGCCACUCUCUCUCUCUUACUUAAUCUGCUCAAAUGAGCCUCUGCUGUUCUUCAGACAUCUGAGGCAUGCUUUCACCAUGGCAUUGGCACUGCUACUCUUUCCGCCUAGAGUCUUCUUUUCUGAGAUGACGAAACUGCUCUUUUACUCCCCUUCAGGCUACUCGAGUACUUCCUCAGCCUUUCCCUGACCAUCCUUUUAAAAAUAGAAACCUCUCUCUCUAAUACUGUCUAUCCUCCACUCUGGUUUACUUUUAUCCAUAGCACUUAUCUUCAGAAAUGCUAUGUAAUUUACUAUUUUGCUUAUUCUUGUCUUGCCUCUACUAGGAAUGUAAUCUAUAAGGGCAGGGAUUUUUCUCUGUUUUCCCAGUGCUUAGUAUAGUGUCUGAUACAAGGUAGGCAUCUCAUAAAUAUUUCUUAAAUGGAGGAAUGAAAGGUACUGCAACCUUUUUCAGGAUUAGGUAUCUCUUCCAUUCUUUAUGGAAAAGCUCUGGACCAUUAUCUGAGGAAAUUCCUGGUCUCCUUUGCAAGUACUUUUGCAAUCACUAUUUAUUUAUUUAUUUAUUUAUUUAGAUGGAAUCUUGCUCUGUUGCCCAGGCUGAAGUGCAGUGGCACAAUCUUGGCUCACUGCAACCUCUGCCUCCUGGGUUCAAGUGAUUCUCGUGCCUCAGCCUCCCAAGUAGAUGGGAUUACAGGUGCGUGCUUCCACGCCUGGUUAAUUUCUGUAUUUUUAGUACAGAUGGCACUUCACCAUGUUGGCCAGGCCAGUCUCGAACUCUUGACUUCAAGUGAUCUUCCUGCCUUGGCCUCUCAAAGUGCUGGGAUUGCAGGUGUGAGCCACCGUGCCCAGCUGCAAUCCAUUUUUUAAAAGAGGUCUUCUAGACCAAGUAUUCUUCCACAUCCAGACUCUAAUUUAUUCUUUGCAAGAAGAUUAUCAUGUUCUCUUAACUAUAUGCAAUACCUUUCUUGAUACUUAAUAGCAACCUCUUCACUUUGAGUUGUAAAUCAUAACAUUUUUUGUACAAAGCAAAGCUGAAACAGGUGAAAGGAAUAGUCUAGGGCAGAAAAUUUUCAAACCUUUUCUAAGGUCUUAGACUCUCUCCACCUCCACAUAUCUUACUGAGAACUUCAGAUAAGAGAAGUGUUUUAUUAUUCAAAAUAAAGGUUUUAUUAUUCAAAAUAAAGCUAUUUUACAUUUGAAUUUAUAGCAUACUCUUAUUAUAAAGUCAAUCUGAACCAUGAAGCUAUUAUAAGGAGUGUAAUAUUGAAAUGAAUGAUUAUGAAUAAAAAUGAUACUCUCUAUAUGUCUCAGCCUCCAAUUUAUUUUUGUAUUGUGAUUUUGUAUUUUGGUUUUGUUGCAGACCAUCAAGGAAAUUUCCAUCCACACAGAUUAGCAGUUGAAAAUGAAGCUGCACACAUACAUGUAAGAGAAGCAAAAAUGUCAGAUGAUAUCAGGAAAAGGUUUGAAUUUCCAAAUUCUCUUAUCCAAUCACAGGCUGUGGGUCAUCUUAUUGCUGCAGUCCUAAAGGAAAAUGGUUUUUCAGAAAAGAUUCACCAAUCUACAAAUCAGACUCCUGCUUUGAACUUGCUGUGGGAGAAGUGUUGCAGUGACAAUGUAGUGGUUCGAACAGCCUGCUGUGAAGGUCUGGUGGCACUCGUUGCUCAGGAUCAUGCAGAGUUCAGCUAUGUUCUCAAUGGGAUACUCAACUUGAUUCCAUCAACCAGAAAUACACAUGGCUUGAUAAAAGCCAUUAUGCACUUACUACAAAUGCAAGCUCUUAAGGAAGGACAAGGUGGGGAAAAGAAUAUUCAGAGUAUAUAUACCAUUAGAAAUCAUCCUCAUCCUUUGAUAACUGUGCUUGAACACAGACCUGAUUGCUGGCCAGUGUUUUUGCAGCAGCUGACAGCGUUUUUCCAGCAGUGCCCUGAAAGGUUAGAAGUUUCAUGCAUUCAAAUAAUGGCACCAUUUCUGUGGUAUCUGUAUUGUGAACCAUCUCAGUUACAAGAAUAUGCUAAACUCCGACUAGCCCUGCUGAAAGUCUUACUUCAACCCCAGGUUCUUUGUGACAAAGAUCAACCAUCAAUACUGGAACAGCAGAUACUUCAACUGUGUUGUGACAUAGUUCCAUGUUUGCAGGUAAAAGAUUUGAUACAGACAACAGAGGCGAUGAUGUUUAUUGAGGAAGUAUGUUUAAGCCUUUUGCGUCAUCCUGUUUUCUGGAAAAUUCAGCUUACCCAGAUGAGUCUUCAGCUGCUGUGUGUCAGUGAAGUCAGCUUAAAGAUAACUGGUGAAUGUUCAUCUUCAAUUCACCUUUUAGAGCACAGUGUUGAACUUCUGAAGGAGGAUUUUCCUGUUGAACUGGUCAUAAUUGGAAUAGCUUUACUACUUCUACAGACUCCAGCAAGUCAGCAGAAGCCAAUCUUAAAUCUAGCUUUGAAGCUCCUCUCUGUUACUGAGGAUCAGAAAAUCCCAAAGUCCUCUCUGCUGCUAGUGAUGCCAAUUCUGCAGAUACUAUCUUCUACUGCCUUGGAAGACUGUAUAUCUGUGGAUGAAGAAGGUCCCUCUAGGCAGCAGUUGGCUCUAAACCUUUUGGAAAUGAUACAGCAGGAAUGUUACAGAGAUGACCACCAAAAGCUCUCCUACAAGCUUGUGUGCCCUGUAACCAGUAUGUAUGGUACAAUAUUUACAGCCUGGAGGAUUCUUGAAGUAAUGACAGACUCGUCUGCUGCAAGUGACUGGUUGGCUUCAGUAGAGUCAUUGCUUCCUAUUACUGCUGUGAUCCCUGCGCCUGCCUUUCUUCUGCUGGCUCACCUCCUUGUUGAAGACAAAGGACAAAAUCUUCACCAAAUACUCAAGGUCACUACAGAAUUAGCCCAAGCAGAUUCCUCCCAGGUGCCAAAUCUGAUUCCAGUUUUGAUGUUCAAAUUGGGAAGACCACUGGAACCUAUAUUAUAUAAUGAUAUAUUGUAUACUUUACCUAAGCUUGGUGUUCACAAGGUGUGUAUAGGACAAAUUCUACGAAUAAUACAACUACUUGGAACCACACCACGACUAAGAGCUGUCACUUUGCGCUUGCUGACAUCUUUGUGGGAAAAGCAGGACCGAGUCUAUCCUGAACUGCAGCGUUUCAUGGCUGUGUCUGAUGUACCUUCUCUUUCGGUGGGCAAGGAAGUCCAAUGGGAGAAACUGAUUGCAAAAGCAGCAUCAAUCAGAGAUAUAUGUAAGCAGAGGCCAUAUCAACAUGGUGCAGAUAUGUUGGCAGCUAUUUCUCAAGUGUUGAAUGAAUGCACCAAGCCUGAUCAAGCUACUCCAGCAGCCUUGGUAUUACAGGGUCUUCAUGCACUCUGUCAAGCUGAGGUUGUUUGCAUUCGCUCCACUUGGAAUGCUCUCUCUCCAAAGCUGAGUUGUGACACAAGACCUCUCAUUCUGAAGACACUGAGUGAACUAUUUUCUCUAGUUCCUUCCUUAACGGUCAAUACAACUGAAUAUGAGAAUUUUAAAGUUCAAGUCCUCAGCUUCCUCUGGACUCAUACUCAAAACAAGGACCCAAUUGUAGCAAAUGCUGCAUAUAGAUCCCUGGCCAACUUUAGUGCAGGAGAACACACCAUUCUUCAUCUGCCUGAAAAGAUAAGACCAGAAAUUCCCAUUCCUGAAGAGUUAGAUGACGAUGAAGAUGUUGAGGAUGUGGAUCUUUCAGUUCCUGGCUCUUGCUAUCUCAAACUGUUGUCACUCACUCCCCCUUUGGUUUUACCAGCUUUGGAGGAAUUUUUUACAUCACUUGUGAAGCAAGAAAUGGUGAAUAUGCCUCGUGGGAUAUAUCACUCUGCAUUAAAAGGAGGUGCCCGCUCAGACCAAGGAAAGACUGUAGCAGGAAUCCCCAAUUUUAUAUUGAAAAUGUAUGAAACAAACAAGCAACCAGGACUGAAACCUGGCCUUGCAGGUGGUAUGUUAUUUUGCUAUGAUGUUUCCAUGUAUCAGAGUAAAGAUGGAAAACCAUUGAACAGACUGAUGGCCAGCAGAGGGCGAAGUUUCAAGCAGACUUCACUUGCUCUUGUACAUGAGGUUCAUAUCCAGCUUUCAGAGUGGCACCGUGCAAUUUUUCUUCCACAGGCCUGGCUUGCAUACAUGAAUCGAGCUUAUCAUGCCAUUUUACAGGGAAGACUAGGAGAGCUGGAGUUGCAGUUAAAACAUGGAAAAGAAGAACCUGAGGAGGUGCAGUACAAAAAAAGCACAGCCUGGCUCUGGGUUAGAGACAUGCUGACUGAUGAGAUCACCAAGGCAGCUGCAAAGGAGAGUCCGGUAGUGAAAGGCAAUGCGCUGUUAGCUCUAAGCAGCCUUGCUGUCGUCGUAUCUAGACAUGAAGCCAGCCUCUCCUCAGACUCUGACGGGCUCCUGGAGGUUCAACCUAAUUUCCUUUCAAUGAAAGAGUGGGUUUCCAUGGUACUUGAUACACUCUUGGUCAUUGUGGAUAGCCAUUACCAACCCAGAGGGCAACUUCUCUCCUGGUUUUAUUAUAAGUCCUAUUCUGGUGAAAACACAGCUAGUGCCAUUGCCCGUUCUGCUGCCGCCACGGCUUUGUCUCUCCUUGUGCCAGUUUUCAUUAUCUCUUGCAAAGAGAAGGUUGAGGAAAUCCUGAACAUGCUGACUGCCAGGUUACCUGGGAAACCAAGUGCUGAUGAGUCUCAAGCCGUGCAAAUCCACAUGGGCCUUGCUUUAGGGAUGUUUCUCUCUCGCUUGUGUGAAGAGAAACUCAGUGAUAUAUCUGGCCAAGAGAUGAACCUUCUUCUGAUGAAGUCGUUGGAUGCCCUGGAAAAUUGCUGCUUUGACACUAGUCUUGAAUACAACACGGGCUGUAUAUUGGGAGUUGGACUUGUUCUGUCCCUCAUGAGCCACAGCAGCCAAAUGCAGUCCCGCGUUCACGUAGCAGCAUUGCUCCGGAAGCUGUCUGCGCACGUAGAUGACAGCGGGAGCCAGAGCAGAACGUUUCAGGAGGUCCUUGCCUACACACUUAGCUGUGUAUGUACAUCAGCGUUCAGUGCUGGAAUUAUUGAGGCUACAGAGGCUGAGGAUGUUAUGAACAAGCUUCGACUGUUAGUGGAGAAUAGCCAGCAGACUUCAGGUUUUGCCCUGGCUUUAGGAAACAUAGUUCAUGGAUUGUCUGUGUGUGGACAUGGAAAAGCUGAAGACUUGGGCAGCAAACUACUCCCUGCCUGGAUCAGAAUUGUUCUAACAGAGGGCACUCCCACAAUGCUUUGUCUGGCAGCUCUUCAUGGCAUGGUGGCCUUGGUAGGCUCUGAAGGGGAUGUAAUGCAGCUGAAAUCAGAAGCCAUCCAGACCUCUCAUUUUCAAGGCAGACUUAAUGAAGUCAUUAGAACCUUAACUCAGGUCAUUAGUGUCUCUGGGGUGAUUGGUCUCCAGUCAAAUGCAGUCUGGCUUCUUGGACAUCUUCAUCUAUCUACUCUAUCCUCAAGUCAAAGUAGAGCCUCUGUUCCUACUGACUAUAGCUACUUGCCUGAAAGCAGUUUUAUUGGAGCAGCUAUUGGCUUCUUCAUUACAGGAGGAAAAAAAGGUCCUGAAUCUGUGCCUCCUUCCCUUCUUAAAGUAGUGAUGAAACCCAUAGCAACUGUUGGAGAAAGCUACCAAUAUCCUCCUGUGAACUGGGCUGCACUUCUCUCUCCACUUAUGAGGCUAAAUUUUGGUGAAGAGAUCCAGCAACUGUGCCUUGAAAUUAUGGUGACCCAGGCACAGUCAUCCCAGAAUGCAGCUGCACUAUUGGGCUUGUGGGUGACACCACCACUGAUCCACAGUCUGAGUCUGAAUACCAAGAGAUAUCUCCUGAUAUCUGCACCUCUGUGGAUAAAACACAUCUCUGAUGAACAGAUCCUGGGUUUUGUUGAAAAUUUAAUGGUGGCAGUUUUUAAAGCAGCUUCCCCACUUGGAAGUCCUGAGCUAUGCCCAAGUGCUUUACACGGUCUGAGCCAGGCCAUGAAACUGCCCAGCCCUGCCCACCACCUCUGGAGUCUGCUCUCUGAAGCUACUGGGAAAAUUUUUGACCUCCUGCCAAAUAAGAUUCGGAGAAAGGAUCUAGAGCUGUAUAUCAGCAUAGCAAAAUGCCUCUUAGAAAUGACAGAUGAUGAUGCCAAUCGGAUCGCCCAGGUUACUAAGAGCAACAUAGAAAAAGCUGCCUUUGUCAAACUGUACUUAGUCUCUCAAGGACGAUUCCCCUUGGUGAACCUGACCGAUAUGCUGAGCGUUGCUGUGCAGCACCGUGAGAAAGAGGUGUUGGCCUGGAUGAUUCUGCACAGCUUAUACCAGGCACGGAUUGUGAGCCAUGCCAAUACGGGCGUUUUGAAGAGAAUGGAGUGGCUCUUGGAACUGAUGGGUUAUAUUAGAAAUGUUGCUUACCAGUCAACAUCCUUUCACAAUACGGCUCUUGACAAGGCUUUGGACUUCUUCUUGCUGAUAUUUGCAACCGCAGUGGUUGCAUGGGCUGACCACACUGCCCCUCUCCUCCUCGGCCUCAGUGCCAGUUGGUUGCCAUGGCAUCAGGAGAAUGGCCCGGCUGGGCCAGUACCAAGCUUCCUUGGCAGGAGUCCAAUGCACAGGGUCACUCUGCAGGAGGUUCUCACUCUCCUUCCCAAUAGCAUGGCUCUGCUGCUGCAGAAAGAGCCAUGGAAGGAACAGACCCAGAAGUUCAUUGACUGGCUAUUCAGCAUCAUGGAAAGCCCUAAAGAAGCCCUCUCAGCACAGUCCAGGGAUCUUUUGAAAGCCACCCUGCUGUCCUUGAGAGUUCUCCCAGAGUUUAAGAAGAAAGCUGUAUGGACCAGAGCAUAUGGUUGGUGAACAGUUUUGCAGUAACCAGCAGCAUUCUCAGCUGGAUGAGGAAAACCAUAUAAGUGGAAGAAGUUUUUCAGAAUUCAUGCCUGGUAUUGCUGAGACAUGAUGCAGAGAGUUAAGGGUCAUGAAAAGAUGGCCACAUCACUGACAGCUUGACACAUGCCUCCUAAGAGAGGAGUGCAUUGCUUUAGUACCCGGGCCAGUUGAGACUGAAACAGGAACUUGGAUUUUCUUUAUUUGGCUUGAGUUCAAUGUGGAGAUUUUCUUUGUGAAAGCUUGAAGAUAUUAUCUUCUCCCUGCUAAAUUCCAGUAAAAUAAUGUUGUCAA